GUGGUCCACCAACAGCUGUGGAGCACAAGGGGCUUGUAGGAUAUAUAAUUCCGUAUUUUUUGGAUCUUCUUGACACUCCUGUCAUUCAGCUAUGUUGCUAAAGCACUAGCUGGAAUUUUUAUGAAAAUAUCAACCACUCAAAUAGAAAGGAGAUUUGAGAUAUCCUCUUCUCUUGUUGGUUUAAUUGAUGGAAGCUUCGAAAUAGGAAAUUUGUUUGUGAUUGUAUUUGUAAGUUACUUUGGAUCUAAACUACACAGACCGAAGUUAAUUGGAAUUGGUUGUUUUCUUAUGGGAACUGGAAGUAUUUUGAUGGCUUUACCACAUUUCUUCAUGGGAUAUUACAGGUAUUCUAAAGAAACCAAUAUUGAUCCAUCAGAAAAUUCAACAUCAAACUUACCAAACUGUUUAAUUAAUCAAAUGUUAUCACUCAAUAGAACACCGUCUGAGAUAAUAGAAAGAGGUUGUGUGAAGGAAUCUGGGUCACACAUGUGGAUCUAUGUCUUCAUGGGUAAUAUGCUUCGUGGCAUAGGGGAAACCCCCAUAGUACCAUUGGGGAUUUCUUACAUUGAUGAUUUUGCAAAAGAAGGACAUUCUUCCUUGUAUUUAGGUACUGUGAAUGUAAUGGGAAUGACUGGUCUAGUUUUUGCCUUUAUGCUGGGAUCUCUGUUUGCUAAAAUGUAUGUGGAUAUCGGAUAUGUGGAUCUGAGCACUAUCAGGAUAACUCCUAAGGACUCUCGUUGGGUUGGAGCUUGGUGGCUUGGUUUCCUUGUGUCUGGAAUAGUAUCCAUUAUUUCUUCUAUACCAUUCUUUUUCUUGCCUCUAAAUCCAAAUAAACCACAGAAAGAAAGGAAAGUUUCACUAUUUUUGCAUGUGCUAAAAACUAAUGAUAAAAGGAAUCAAAUAGCUAAUUUGACCAACCGAAGAAAAUAUAUUACCAAAAAUGUGACUGGCUUUUUCCAGUCUUUGAAAAGCAUCCUUACCAAUCCCCUGUAUGUUAUAUUUGUAAUUUUUACAUUGUUACACAUGAGCAGCUACAUUGCUUCUCUUACUUAUAUCAUUAAAAUGGUGGAGCAACAGUAUGGUUGGUCUGCAUCUAAGACUAACUUUUUGUUGGGAGUCCUCGCCCUACCUGCUGUUGCAAUUGGCAUGUUUUCAGGAGGAUAUAUCAUUAAAAAAUUCAAAUUGUCUUUAGUUGGACUUGCCAAAUUGGCAUUUUGUUCUGCAACAGUGCAUCUCUUAUCUCAAGUUUUAUAUUUCUUUCUAAUCUGUGAAAGCAAAUCAGUUGCCGGCCUAACCUUGACCUAUGAUGGAGUGCAAUUGUGAUGAAAGUCAAUGGGAACCCGUCUGUGGAAACAAUGGAAUAACUUACCUGUCACCUUGUCUAGCAGGAUGCAAAUCUUCAAGUGGUAAUAAAGAG